GCCCGCACCUGCUGGCUCACCUCCGAGCCACCUCUGCUGCGCACCGCAGCCUCGGACCUACAGCCCAGGAUACUUUGGGACUUGCCGGCGCUCAGAAACGCGCCCAGACGGCCCCUCCACCUUUUGUUUGCCUAGGGUCGCCGAGAGCGCCCGGAGGGAACCGCCUGGCCUUCGGGGACCACCAAUUUUGUCUGGAACCACCCUCCCGGCGUAUCCUACUCCCUGUGCCGCGAGGCCAUCGCUUCACUGGAGGGGUCGAUUUGUGUGUAGUUUGGUGACAAGAUUUGCAUUCACCUGGCCCAAACCCUUUUUGUCUCUUUGGGUGACCGGAAAACUCCACCUCAAGUUUUCUUUUGUGGGGCUGCCCCCCAAGUGUCGUUUGUUUUACUGUAGGGUCUCCCCGCCCGGCGCCCCCAGUGUUUUCUGAGGGCGGAAAUGGCCAAUUCGGGCCUGCAGUUGCUGGGCUUCUCCAUGGCCCUGCUGGGCUGGGUGGGUCUGGUGGCCUGCACCGCCAUCCCGCAGUGGCAGAUGAGCUCCUAUGCGGGUGACAACAUCAUCACGGCCCAGGCCAUGUACAAGGGGCUGUGGAUGGACUGCGUCACGCAGAGCACGGGGAUGAUGAGCUGCAAAAUGUACGACUCGGUGCUCGCCCUGUCCGCGGCCUUGCAGGCCACUCGAGCCCUAAUGGUGGUCUCCCUGGUGCUGGGCUUCCUGGCCAUGUUUGUGGCCACGAUGGGCAUGAAGUGCACGCGCUGUGGGGGAGACGACAAAGUGAAGAAGGCCCGUAUAGCCAUGGGUGGAGGCAUAAUUUUCAUCGUGGCAGGUCUUGCCGCCUUGGUAGCUUGCUCCUGGUAUGGCCAUCAGAUUGUCACAGACUUUUAUAACCCUUUGAUCCCUACCAACAUUAAGUAUGAGUUUGGCCCUGCCAUCUUUAUUGGCUGGGCAGGGUCUGCCCUAGUCAUCCUGGGAGGUGCACUGCUCUCCUGUUCCUGUCCUGGGAAUGAGAGCAAGGCUGGGUACCGUGUACCCCGCUCUUACCCUAAGUCCAACUCUUCCAAGGAGUAUGUGUGACCUGGGAUCUCCUUGCCCCAGCCUGACAGGCUAUGGGAGUGUCUAGAUGCCUGAAAGGGCCUGGGGCUGAGCUCAGCCUGUGGGCAGGGUGCCGGACAAAGGCCUCCUGGUCACUCUGUCCCUGCACUCCAUGUAUAGUCCUCUUGGGUUGGGGGUGGGGGGGUGCCGUUGGUGGGAGAGACAAAAAGAGGGAGAGUGUGCUUUUUGUACAGUAAUAAAAAAUAAGUAUUGGGAAGCAGGCUUUUUUCCCUUCAGGGCCUCUGCUUUCCUCCCGUCCAGAUCCUUGCAGGGAGCUUGGAACCUUAGUGCACCUACUUCAGUUCAGAACACUUAGCACCCCACUGACUCCACUGACAAUUGACUAAAAGAUGCAGGUGCUCGUAUCUCGACAUUCAUUCCCACCCCCCUCUUAUUUAAAUAGCUACCAAAGUACUUCUUUUUUAAUAAAAAAAUAAAGAUUUUUAUUAGGUA